ACUUGUUUGCUGCUGGAGCCGCGGCGUUCUCCUCGGGCCCGGGCCGCGCCCGUGGGUGCUCCGGACCGGACUCCGCGGGCGCAGCUGUCCCGACGCUGAGCUGGGGACCCGUGGGGUUCUCGGAGAGGGGCAGAGACCCAAGGUCACAGAGGUCCCGGAACGCCAGCCACAGCCACCUGGGCAGGAGCUGGGGCGGCGUGAGGGACACAGGCGCGAGGGCACCCCCCCACCCUGCUGCCUGCUGCCCCGCGCCGGCCUGGGCGACCCCGGCGUGACACCCGGUCCUGGGACUCCCUUCGGCGCCCAGAACGCGUCGGCAGCAUCCGGCCUGUGGGAGGGAGGGAGGGAGGGAGGGAGGCGUCCUGAGGCAGCCCGGCCCCUGCUGCCCUGCGCUCCCGUGCGGCCCCAGCCCGUCCUCCGCACCCCGAGCUUCCCGGGCUGGCCCCCGCCCUCCGCGUGCGCCCAGCGCUCUUGCAGGCGGAGGGUGCGGGCCGAUCCCCCCGCGCCGCCCCGCUGGCCGGUCUUGGCGAUGGUGGGGCCGAGUAGGGCCUGAGCCCUCGGAGGCGCUCUUCCCCCGGCCUGGAGGUUCCGGGAGAGUGGCCUCCUGCCUGCCUGCCUGCUGGAGGCCUAAGCGGGCUGAGUCCAGCUGCCCCUCGGCCUCCCCGCCACCUGCUUCCCUGUUUCCCUGUCCCGGAGCGCCAUCCCAGAGAGGCUGCGGAGGAGGGCGAGGGAACCUGGACCCUUCCGGACCCUCCGAGCUCCAUCUACCCACGCCGAGCUCUGCCAGCACGCCCGCCUGCCGCACUUGUUCUGCCAGAGCAGAGGCCUGGGCUGGCCUUGGGGCUCCAGGGCCAGAGAGGCAUCACCCAGGGACUCUGCGGGGAGCCUGCCUGACACGGGAGGGAUGGCUGGGCAGAGGCCGUGCUGGCGGGGUAUAUUAUCAAGGGCAGGCAUGGCUGGGGCAGAAUUCUCUGUAGGUAGGGUGUGUCACCUGGGGAAGGACAUUCUGGGUCCUUGGCAGGGUGACUAUAAAAGCACACUGGCAUGAAGGCCUAGGUGGGGCCAUAUCUGAAGGGCUGGGGCAUGCUCUUUGAGUCGUGGGUAGAGCCGUGAGCCCUUGCCCUUUGUCCUGAGCCAGUGUGUGCCUCCCGCAGCAGCCACAUGCCCGCGGAUUGAUGUCAGGAGCCACCUCUGCAAGCCUGGCUUACCACAGGGAGCCAGGCUCCAGGACAGCAGAGUGAGGGAGAGGCACUGGCUCCAUGGCACCCACUGUGUCUGGGGGGCAUCCAGGAGGCUGGCUCUCUGAGGGCCUGGGGAACAGGAGAGCAAAGAAGGGGAGCACUUAGAUUCACGAGCCCAGCCCCUAGGGGAUAGAAGCCUAAGGAUCCUGUGAGGUAUGAGUAUGGGGUGACAUAGGCCUCCCUUGUCGAGGGGCUGUCACUGUUUCUGUGGUGACCCAGUAGUACCAGGUCUUUGGAGGCCUCAAGAGAAGCUGGGAAUCUGGGCUCUUAUGUGAACCCAUCUCGUUGUCACAUGUAGAAAAUCUGUCUUAAACCCCUGGUGAAACCAGACGUAGCCAGUCGGAGGCCAGAUUGGAACCUGGCCUCCACUUUGCAGCCAGCGGGGGUCCAGGAACUUGAGGGAAGGACCCAGGAAGUGGAAUCUGCAGGGAAGGAAGGAGGUGGGCAGGGAACCAGAGAGGAAGGGCAGCAGGUGUGGGCAUCAUCCUGGAAACGCAAGGUCAAGCCCAGGACGGCCUCUUAGACCAACGCAAAAUGGACCCUGGAGAAGGGUUUGGGGCCCAAUUUCCUAUCUAGCCCGUGCAGCAGCUCUGCCAGCGCUCAAACUGUGGCCCUCGGUCAAGCACCUGCUGAGGAUCUGCCCAGGGAGGCAGACCCUUGGGGGCAGCCCGGGGUCUCAGCCAUGCAGCGCUCCCAGCCUUCAGGCUGUCCGCCUCCCCAGGCCUGGACUUCAGCAAUGAUGGACACCCUUACUCCUAGGAGGUUGCAGGGUCUGGAGAGGAGGCAGACACCUGCCACACACAUGCAUGGUGACAGCAGACCGUUAACGGGCCUGAUAUCUGCCUAUGCCCCUCUGAGCCUGUCCCUUUUCCCUGAGUACAAGGCACAAAGGUUGUGCCCCAGCUUGGCUCUUUAAUCUUUCCCCAACCAAGAGGGAAGCAGGGGGAACUGUGGUUUGUGGGCCCCAGGAUGUCCUAAUGACUCGCCUCCAGGGGAGGGUGACACAGCCUCCAGGCCUCAUUGCUGCUGCUCUUAACAACGUGGUCCUGAGGCAAGAAAGUGUGGCAGGGGCUCCCAGGCUGGUCCCUCUCCUCACCUGAGCUGCCUCCCCAGCUCCCGAGGGUUAUAGGGUGCCAGCAUGGCUUGGCAGAGCCCUGGCAUAGGGCCUGGCCCAUGGGGAGGCAGUCACAGAGUUGGACCCACAGUCAGAGAAGCUGAGGGCAAGGCGGGUGGAGGAGCUGGCAGGCGGGGGAGGCUGCCCAGGGCCAGGGCCUGCAGUGUGUAGGGAAAUGACAGAAGGGUUGGUGUGGGCGGGAGCCCGUGGGGCCCUUUAUCUCCUGGUAAACAGGACCCGGGGGAGAGGGGAGGCCCCUAGGAAGGAAGCGAGGGUAAGGCGCAGGCUGUUGCCAGGGUGAUUCAGGCAGCAUCACCCACCACUGCCCACCCAGCCUGUCCAUCUGAGGCAGUCGUGUGGGACAGAGAAAGCCAGGGUGGGGCUCGGGGGUGGGGGUGGGCAGUGGCUGUAAGUAGGCAAGCGGGGACUGGCAUCUAGGCAGGAGGGAGGCGCACCUGCAGGUGCAGGUGGCUCUGAACCCAUUCCUGAUGGCUCUCUAGGCCUCUGCACCUCCAGUCCCAUCCCUGUGGGCGAGUGCUGCCUACACCUGGUGUCACCCAGCAAUGGGUGAGCCCUGGGGAUAGCCAGCUCUGCAUUCAAGGGGUUAGGUUUCCAGGGUAACCGAGCCCCUGAGCCCAGCGUGGAGCCUGGCAGAGCCAGUAAUCUGACUCCCCUUUCCCUCCCGCCAGGGGCUGUCCAGAGGCUCCGCUUUGCCUCAGCCUUUAGCCCCAGAGAGGCAGGGUGUGGAGGGUGGGGGCUGGCUUCUUGGGUAAGAGAUGCCUCAGGGAAGAUCUACCUGGCUCCCUGCUCCUUAAACCUUUCCCUCCUGCCCAGGUCCACCCCUUCCUCUUCCCUGGUCACUUGGCACUUCGACCUCCUGCCCGUUUCGGAAAGGGGUGUGCCCUGAGGUGACUGAACUUUGCCUGAUCAUGACCUUGAUCAUGCACAGGGCUGCUGGUGGGGUGAGGCCAUCCCACGCAACUCUGGGGUCUGUGAAGCCACCAAGGAUCAAGGAAUGGAAGAGCUGCCUGAGUGUAGAGGGAGUUCGGUCAGGCUUCUUAAACUUGGAGACUUGGAAACAGAAGGCCUUGUAGGCCACAUAGGUUUUCAGAGACUCGCCUGGCAGAGGCCUGGAGCGUCCUGCUGCGUGGACUGUGGGCACCGAGCCACCAGGAGGCGACGUUGUGGACGUUUACCAGCGGGAGUUCCUGGCGCUGCGCGAUCGGUUGCACGCAGCUGAGCAGGAGAGCCUCAAGCGCUCCAAGGAGCUCAACCUGGUGCUGGACGAGAUCAAGAGGGCCGUGUCAGAAAGGCAGGCGCUGCGAGACGGAGACGGCAAUCGCACCUGGGGCCGCCUAACAGAGGACCCCCGAUUGAAGCCGUGGAACGGCUCACACCGGCACGUGCUGCACCUGCCCACCGUCUUCCAUCACCUGCCACACCUGCUGGCCAAGGAGAGCAGUCUGCAGCCCGCGGUGCGCGUGGGCCAGGGCCGCACCGGAGUGUCGGUGGUGAUGGGCAUCCCGAGCGUGCGGCGCGAGGUGCACUCGUACCUGACUGACACUCUGCACUCGCUCAUCUCCGAGCUGAGCCCGCAGGAGAAGGAGGACUCGGUCAUCGUGGUGCUGAUCGCCGAGACUGACUCACAGUACACUUCGGCAGUGACAGAGAACAUCAAGGCCUUGUUCCCCACGGAGAUCCAUUCUGGGCUCCUGGAGGUCAUCUCACCCUCCCCCCACUUCUACCCUGACUUCUCCCGCCUCCGAGAGUCCUUUGGGGACCCCAAGGAGAGAGUCAGGUGGAGGACCAAACAGAACCUCGAUUACUGCUUCCUCAUGAUGUACGCGCAGUCCAAAGGCAUCUACUACGUGCAGCUGGAGGAUGACAUCGUGGCCAAGCCCAACUACCUGAGCACCAUGAAGAACUUUGCACUGCAGCAGCCUUCAGAGGACUGGAUGAUCCUGGAGUUCUCCCAGCUGGGCUUCAUUGGUAAGAUGUUCAAGUCGCUGGACCUGAGCCUGAUUGUAGAGUUCAUUCUCAUGUUCUACCGGGACAAGCCCAUCGACUGGCUCCUGGACCAUAUUCUGUGGGUGAAAGUCUGCAACCCCGAGAAGGAUGCGAAGCACUGUGACCGGCAGAAAGCCAACCUGCGGAUCCGCUUCAAACCGUCCCUCUUCCAGCACGUGGGCACUCACUCCUCGCUGGCUGGCAAGAUCCAGAAACUGAAGGACAAAGACUUUGGAAAGCAGGCGCUGCGGAAGGAGCAUGUGAACCCGCCAGCAGAGGUGAGCACGAGCCUGAAGACAUACCAGCACUUCACCCUGGAGAAAGCCUACCUGCGCGAGGACUUCUUCUGGGCCUUCACCCCUGCCGCGGGGGACUUCAUCCGCUUCCGCUUCUUCCAACCUCUAAGACUGGAGCGGUUCUUCUUCCGCAGUGGGAACAUCGAGCACCCGGAGGACAAGCUCUUCAACACGUCUGUGGAGGUGCUGCCCUUCGACAACCCUCAGUCAGACAAGGAGGCCCUGCAGGAGGGCCGCACCGCCACCCUCCGGUACCCUCGGAGCCCCGACGGCUACCUCCAGAUCGGCUCCUUCUACAAGGGAGUGGCAGAGGGAGAGGUGGACCCAGCCUUCGGCCCUCUGGAAGCACUGCGCCUCUCGAUCCAGACGGACUCCCCUGUGUGGGUGAUUCUGAGCGAGAUCUUCCUGAAAAAGGCCGACUAAGCUGCGGGCUUCUGAGGGUACCCUGUGGCCAGCCCUGAAGCCCACAUUUCUGGGGGUGUCGUCACUGCCGUCCCCGGAGGGCCAGAUACGGCCCCGCCCAAAGGGUUCUGCCUGGCGUCGGGCUUGGGCCGGCCUGGGGUCCGCCGCUGGCCCGGAGGCCCUAGGAGCUGGUGCUGCCCCCGCCCGCCGGGCCGCGGAGGAGGCAGGCGGCCCCCACACUGUGCCUGAGGCCCGGAACCGUUCGCACCCGGCCUGCCCCAGUCAGGCCGUUUUAGAAGAGCUUUUACUUGGGCGCCCGCCGUCUCUGGCGCGAACACUGGAAUGCAUAUACUACUUUAUGUGCUGUGUUUUUUAUUCUUGGAUACAUUUGAUUUUUUCACGUAAGUCCACAUAUACUUCUAUAAGAGCGUGACUUGUAAUAAAGGGUUAAUGAAG